AGUGCCCGCGCAGCGUUGAGUUGCACAGCGGUAUUCUCACCAGGCCCUGCAAUCGGUGGGCCACAGUGCCGGCCACAGAGAUGGUGGAAGGACCAGGCUGUACUCUGAAUGGAGAGAAGAUUCGCGCGCGGGUGCUCCCGGGCCAGGCGGUGACCGGCGUGCGGGGAAGCGCUCUGCGGAGUCUGCAGGGCCGCGCCUUGCGGCUCGCAGCCUCCACGGUUGUGGUCUCCCCGCAGGCUGCUGCACUGAAUAAUGAUUCCAGCCAGAAUGUCUUGAGCCUGUUUAAUGGAUAUGUUUACAGUGGCGUGGAAACUUUGGGGAAGGAGCUCUUUAUGUACUUUGGACCAAAAGCUUUACGGAUUCAUUUCGGAAUGAAAGGCUUCAUCAUGAUUAAUCCACUUGAGUAUAAAUAUAAAAAUGGAGCUUCUCCUGUUUUGGAAGUGCAGCUCACCAAAGAUUUGAUUUGUUUCUUUGACUCAUCAGUAGAACUCAGAAACUCAAUGGAAAGCCAACAGAGAAUAAGAAUGAUGAAAGAAUUAGAUGUAUGUUCACCUGAAUUUAGUUUCUUGAGAGCAGAAAGUGAAGUUAAAAAACAGAAAGGCCGGAUGCUAGGUGAUGUGCUAAUGGAUCAGAACGUAUUGCCUGGAGUAGGGAACAUCAUCAAAAAUGAAGCUCUCUUUGACAGUGGUCUCCACCCAGCUGUUAAAGUUUGUCAAUUAACAGAUGAACAGAUCCAUCACCUCAUGAAAAUGAUACGUGAUUUCAGCAUUCUCUUUUACAGGUGCCGUAAAGCAGGACUUGCUCUCUCUAAACACUAUAAGGUUUACAAGCGUCCUAAUUGUGGUCAGUGCCACUGCAGAAUAACUGUGUGCCGCUUUGGGGACAAUAACAGAAUGACAUAUUUCUGUCCUCACUGUCAAAAAGAAAAUCCUCAACAUGUUGACAUAUGCAAGCUACCGACUAGAAAUACUAUAAUCAGUUGGACAUCUAGCAGGGUGGAUCAUGUUAUGGACUCCGUGGCUCGGAAGUCGGAAGAGCACUGGACCUGUGUGGUGUGUACUUUAAUCAAUAAGCCCUCUUCUAAGGCAUGUGAUGCUUGCUUGACCUCAAGGCCUAUUGAUUCAGUGCUCAAGAGUGAAGAAAAUUCUACUGUCUUUAGCCACUUAAUGAAGUACCCGUGUAAUACUUUUGGAAAACCUCAUACAGAAGUCAAGAUCAACAGAAAAACUGCAUUUGGAACUACAACUCUUGUCUUGACUGAUUUUAGCAAUAAAUCCAGUACUUUGGAAAGAAAAACAAAGCAAAACCAGAUACUAGAUGAGGAGUUUCAAAACUCUCCUCCUGCUAGUGUUUGUUUGAAUGAUAUACAGCACCCCUCCAAGAAGACAACAAACGAUAUAACUCAACCAUCCAGCAAAGUAAACAUAUCACCUACAAUCAGUUCAGAAUCUAAAUUAUUUAGUCCAGCACAUAAAAAACCGAAAACAGCCCAAUACUCAUCACCAGAGCUUAAAAGCUGCAACCCUGGAUAUUCUAACAGUGAACUUCAAAUUAAUAUGACAGAUGGCCCUCGUACCUUAAAUCCUGACAGCCCUCGCUGCAGUAAACACAACCGCCUCUGCAUUCUCCGAGUUGUGGGGAAGGAUGGGGAAAACAAGGGCAGGCAGUUUUAUGCCUGUCCUCUACCUAGAGAAGCACAAUGUGGAUUUUUUGAAUGGGCAGAUUUGUCCUUCCCAUUCUGCAACCAUGGCAAGCGUUCCACCAUGAAAACAGUAUUGAAGAUUGGACCUAACAAUGGAAAGAAUUUUUUUGUGUGUCCUCUUGGGAAGGAAAAACAAUGCAAUUUUUUCCAGUGGGCAGAAAAUGGGCCAGGAAUAAAAAUUAUUCCUGGAUGCUAAUAUCUGUAGAUUCUCUGGCAUUUAGUCUCUUCAAACUGUGUAUAAUGUUUGGUCCUCCUCUGUUUCAUAGAAAAGUCAUAGAAUAUCUAUGAUACAUUGAAAAGUUACUGCAAUAUUUGAGAACUGUUCUUUUUUUUUCUUGUGUGUGCCAUCUUUCCAUUGUUGGCUACGUCUUUUCUUUUGCCUUGAUGAACGUUCUAUGUAUUUCAUCGGAUAUACAGCAUAUUCCAUUUAGGAUGUGUAUUUAAUGCAUUUAGUAAUGACGAUAAAGUGUUUUUAGUAUGCUUUUAGUCUCUUGUAACUGGGGAGAAGCAGUGUUUUUUUUUUAGGAAAGGAUUAUGCGACACAAUAAAAUAAGAUAUUCUGUCUGUAGUGAAUACAUUUCUCAUGUACUAACACUAUUUAUAAUAUAUGAUUAAAGAUAUUUCUUGUUUUAUUAAAUAAUAAGAAAUAAGAUCUCCUUUAUGAACAAGUCUAUUUUUAAAAUUCUGUUCAACCAACAUUAAGUUCCUGUUAGAGGCUGGGGCUAUGCCAAACCUUGUAUGACUUCAAAUUUGUGUUCUCAUGUAAAGUGAUGUGGAUGCAGACUAUAAAAGUAACAUUUAAGAAAAGAAGAACUUGCGUGUAGGCGUUUAAAAGAGAGGUUGAUUUAUAUUUUUCUAACGCCCUCUCCCCGCUGCUUGUAUUUAAAUUUUAGCACAGAUCACUAUGAUUGUUCCUCCUCGAUAAAAAGUCACUCUUAAGGUGUUUCUGUAUGCUUGUAAAAAAAAGUCCUUUCAGAGCUGGUUGAAUCUGUUUUUUUUAAAGGACAGCACAAAGGUGGCUUGAACCACUUUCCCGUUCUACCACUAAUUUUUCCAUGCAGAGCUAUAGAAGUUAACAGCAUAUGAAAUUACUGGCAAGAACAAAACAUGUUUUAUAGUUUUAUAAGUAUUUUGUUUUGACUCUACACUGAAAAGACAGGACCAACCUAGGAUGAGUGAUCUUCACCCAAAUUGCUCAACAGGGCAGUGACUCUACAGAACAGACCAGGAACUGGACUGGACAGUUGACAAUCUUAGCUGCACUGAUGUGAAGUACAUAGAGAGUACAUUAGGAAGGAAACUGCAAGCUAAUUGUGCAAUAAAGAGGAAAAAAGGUCCACUGCAAAAAGGACUUCCAGGAAGUCUGGUCUCCAAAAAUGUGCAUGUUAAUUACACGGAAAUAGAGGAAAUAACAAUGGCGAUAACCUUAAAGAAGGACCUGAACUACACCCUACAGCAAGGGGAUUAAGGAUGGAAGGAACAGUGCAAAAGCUGUUUUUGUUUAGGGAACAGAGUCCAGAAGUUCAAAAUAAAAGUAUUUGGAAGAGAUGCUGGGCAGAGAUUGUGGCUUCAAGUGCAUGGAAACACUGACUAUAUAGUGUUUCUGGAGGAGCAGAUUGUAGGGUCACAUGGUUUCACCCCAUGAUGGAUCCAAGUAGUUCCAGAGUCACAUUCAUUGAAAUCUAUUCGAGAAGGGGUAAAUCCUGUACUCAAAGGAGGGCCUGGGGAACAGCAGAGAAUGGAAGAAACCUAUUGUUCUACUUUCUAUGUAUUAUUUGAAUUGUAUUGACUUCUCUAAUAAAAGAGUAAUGAGGGAGGAAAAAAGAAGUUAAAAAGAGAUGAAGAGCUGGGUGCAGUGGCUCAUGCCUGUAAUCCCAGCAUGCUGGGAGGCCGAAGCAGGCAGAUCACUUGAGGUCAGGAGUUUGAGAUCAGCCUGGCCAACACGGUAAAACCCCAUCUCUACUAAAAAUACAAAAACUAGUCUGGUGUGGUGGCGAGCACCUGUAGUCCCAGCUAUGUGGGAGGCUGAGGUGGGAGGAUCACUUGAGCCAGGGAGGUCGAGGCUGCAGUGAGCCAUGAUCAUACCACUGCCCUCCAGCCUGGGCAACAGAGCGAGACCCUGUCUCAAAAGAAAAAAUAAGUGAUGAAGAAAAAAGUGAAGACAAAAAAAAAAGAUCCUCUGACUGCGAAUAGAAAGGGAAGGAUGAAGAGAACACCUAAAGUAUCUAUAUUUAUGUGGGCACUUGGCAUCUGUUUUUGGUAAUCAGUAACACAAAUAUAUGUAAUCAACAAAAGAACAGUCUUAUAAAUUUUUAAAACUACAUACUAGCAUUUUGUACUAAAUGCUAUCAUAAAAUGCAAAACUGCAAAACAAAUUCAAAGUCUCAUUACAACAAUUCCAUAUCUACCUUCCAUAUUAACAUAUCUAUGUCACUCCCAAUCGCUAGCAUGAGCAUCUUGGUUUACCUAUUAAUAAAUACUUGCCUGCUUGUAA